ACUUCCGCUCGGAGGGCGGCCUCAAACGGCCAAUCCCGGCGCGCAGCGGCCCCGGCCUGCCCGCCCCCGGGGCCUACGCGCGCCUGGGGAGGGCGCGGGAACCUGGGAAUGCCCAAAAGCGCGAAGGAAAGCGGGCACGGGAGCCCAGAGCCCUUAAGACUCUCCUGAGGUCCUGGGCGCGACUUUUCCCUGUGCAGCCCCCAGCCGGGUUAGCGCGCCCCCAAGCCCCCAACCCCACGACCCUAACACCUUUACCAGGUGGGAUUACUAGCUUUUCUUCAACAUCGAUGGCCCCCCGCACGCUUCCCAGGCCCCGUGGGCCUUAGCCAGGCCGCAGCUCGACCCUGCCUCUGGCCUCGCGCACCCCAGAACCCGCCGACCCCGGUCCCCCAAGACCCCAGCUCACACCAACAGGUGUUCCCCGGGAGGCUCCCCGCGCAGGACGCCCUCCCGGGCUCGUAGACCCGUACCCUUCUCUAGCGCGUAGUCCUUCAGUGCCAUCGCUGCCGAGGGCCGUGCGGCCGCGCUUGGCGGGCUCAGAGGUCUUGCUCCUGGGGAAGCUGAGAAUCUCCGCGCGGUGGACUGUGGCCGGCCAACCGAAAUUGGCGCGAAACGUCGCCCCCCACGUGACCGGCGCCACUGCGUGCGGGCCAAUCGGACAAGGCGGCCUUCUUCACCUCCCGCUAGCCGCAAGCCAAUCACCAACGGCCAUGAUUUCCCAAUUCUUCAUUCUGUCCUCCAAGGGGGACCCGCUCAUCUACAAAGACUUCCGCGGGGACAGUGGCGGCCGGGAUGUGGCCGAGCUCUUCUACCGGAAGCUGACGGGACUGCCAGGAGACGAGUCCCCGGUUGUCAUGCAUCACCAUGGCCGUCAUUUCAUUCACAUCAGACACAGCGGCCUCUAUUUGGUGGUCACAACUUCAGAAAACGUUUCUCCCUUCAGCCUCCUAGAACUGCUCUCCAGGUUGGCCACCCUUCUGGGCGAUUACUGUGGCUCCCUGGGCGAGGGGACCAUCUCCCGCAAUGUGGCUCUGGUAUACGAACUCCUGGAUGAAGUGCUGGACUAUGGCUAUGUACAGACCACAUCCACGGAGAUGCUGAGGAAUUUCAUCCAGACGGAAGCUGUGGUCAGCAAGCCCUUCAGCCUCUUUGACCUCAGCAGCGUUGGCUUGUUUGGGGCUGAGACACAACAGAGCAAAGUGGCCCCCAGCAGUGCAGCCAGCCGCCCCGUCCUGUCCAGUCGCUCUGACCAGAGCCAAAAGAAUGAAGUUUUUUUGGAUGUGGUCGAGAGAUUGUCUGUACUGAUAGCAUCUAAUGGAUCCCUGCUGAAGGUGGAUGUGCAGGGAGAGAUUCGGCUCAAGAGCUUCCUUCCUAGCGGCUCUGAGAUGCGCAUUGGCUUGACGGAAGAGUUUUGUGUGGGGAAGUCAGAGCUGAGAGGUUAUGGGCCAGGAAUCCGGGUCGAUGAAGUCUCGUUUCACAGCUCUGUGAAUCUGGACGAAUUUGAGUCUCAUCGAAUCCUCCGCUUGCAACCACCUCAGGGCGAGCUGACUGUGAUGCGGUACCAACUCUCCGAUGACCUCCCCUCACCGCUCCCCUUCCGGCUCUUCCCCUCUGUGCAGUGGGACCGAGGCUCAGGCCGGCUCCAGGUUUAUCUAAAGUUGCGAUGUGACCUGCUCUCAAAGAGCCAAGCCCUCAAUGUCAGGCUGCACCUCCCCCUGCCUCGAGGGGUGGUCAGCCUGUCUCAGGAGCUGAGCAGCCCAGAGCAGAAGGCUGAGCUGGCAGAGGGAGCCCUUCGCUGGGACCUGCCUCGGGUGCAAGGAGGCUCUCAACUCUCAGGCCUUUUCCAGAUGGACGUCCCAGGGCCCCCAGGACCUCCCAGCCAUGGGCUCUCCACCUCGGCCUCUCCUCUGGGGCUGGGCCCUGCCAGUCUCUCCUUCGAGCUUCCCCGGCACACGUGCUCUGGCCUCCAGGUCCGAUUCCUCAGGCUGGCCUUCAGGCCAUGCGGCAAUGCCAACCCCCACAAGUGGGUGCGACACCUAAGCCACAGCGACGCCUAUGUCAUUCGGAUCUGAGGCUCCCCAAACGAGGACACGACGGCCAAGGUGGCAGUUUGUCCCACGGGAGGACAGUCGUUUCUUUUCCAGCCUCCUGGCCUUCGGACUCUGAAUCUGGGCAGGAAGAGUCCUCAGUCCCAAGACCAGGAGGGGGCAAUGGGCCCAGCCUUUCUGUGGUAUCUGAUGCAGGAAGGACUGCAGUGGAUCAGAACUUACAAACCAAACUUUUAUUCUGAGAAACUGGCUGUACAAUAUCUAAAAAGAAAGUGACAUGAAGGAAGCAAUCUACAACUUCCUUCCGCUUAGCGAGCAUGCAUGUGUGUACGUGCACGUGUGUACAUGUCUGCAUGUGUGGGAAUCCGGGGGCUGGCAGGUGGAGCAUCACGGAGCAGGCUGAGGGGAGCCGGAGUUGGGCUGGGAGCCAUUGGCUUUUGGAGUCCCUGGAGCUGGAGGGGGACUGUCCCCAGCCUCCUGCUUCCCCCCACAAAGGGCACUGCCGCUGAGUGGGGACGGGGACGAUGCCGGGGGAGGAACUGGAGAAGGAUGGGAGGUGGGGCCUCCUUUGCCCUCCCCUGUUGGGGGAAGUGAGACCACGAUGUACUUCUGGACACUCCCAGGACCAGAGGGAGCAGUGCUGGGGGGUGCGGUGGUGGCGGUGGAGACCAACUUGACGAUGGGCUGCACGCUGGGGACGGUGGUGGUGACGGGCGAAGUGGUGGUGGAACCUGAGCCGGGGGCCGAGGUGCUGAGGGACAGGACCUGGAUAGAAAGGAAAGGCAGGCCGCUUGCCCUGUGCCCUCCCUGCCCCCCAGAGGCCUGGCGAGGACGCUUCACUCGCUCCCUGCCUGAACAAGUUGUUCCUGUAGUUCACCCUGUAGACAGCUAUGGCUGGAGACCUUGUUCAUGCAGGGCAGCUACAGCCCUGCAGGACCCUGGUGGGCGCCUCUUCCAGCUCUUGACUUGGGGCCCAGAGGGGACUGUGCUCUACUCCUGGGCCUCCCCAGGGUGCUCUGAGGUAACCCAGGCCCUCCAGAUGCUCCCUGUCCCACAGCUCUGCAUACCUGCUGGGUGGAUGGGGCGCUGGAGGACGAUGACAUUACAAUAAACUUGGUUGGAGGAGGGGAAGGCUGUGGUGGGGCAGCCGCUCGUGCAGACACCAGUGUCUGGACAGGAAGUGCGAUGGAGCCAGGAACCUUCAGCAAGCCAGGGGUGCGAGGGCCAGGCUGUGGGGCCUGCGAGAGGGUCAGCGUGGGCCGGGGCUGCGGGGAGAAGAGGAAAGGGGGAAGUGGCACCAUCUACUAAGAAGAGGAGUCUGAAGGGAGAGGCCUGGGCUCCCCUCGCUCUUCCUCAGUGGCUCUCACUAGGGCUGGGGCAUCCUCACUCAGGGCCUGGUUGCCCUGAGACUACUGACUGAGGGCACAUGUGGCUGUGUGCAAGUGCCUGUCCCACACAGGGGUUCUCCUCUGCUUCCUCCUAUUCCUCCUCCCCACCCGGCCACGGACCUGCGUGAUGGUCAGAGUGGUCCUGUUGACCUGCUGAGCCUGCAGAGCAGCCUGGGCCCGAGCCUUGACCACCUGGGAGCAGAGGAGGGGCCCAAGGGACCCGAAUUCUGCCCGAUAGGCGUCCUGAUUGUCAGGCGGUGGGCGCAGCUUUGCCAGAACAGGAGCACAGUGUUUCUGCAGAACAGAAAAAAAGCCAGGUAGAGGGAGGGCUGGGGAAAAAAGCCAGGUAGAGGGAGGGCUGGUGACACUCUUGAGAAGAACCUUGGGGAUGGGGUAAAAAAGGACAUUCCUUAUCAUCUCAGUGCCCCUGUUGAAGGCCAAAUUAUGCUGAACUAUUAGUGUGUGUACAGAACACUGUGGGCUUUCUCAUAAGAAAAGAUGGGCACGGGGCCAGGUGCAGCAUCUUAGGCCUGUAUCCCAGCACUUGGGAGGCUGAGGUGGGUGGAUCACUUGAGGUCAAGAGCCUGGCCAAAAUGGAGAAACCUCAUCUCCACUAAAAAUACAAAAACUAGCCAGGCAUGGUGGCACGCACCUGUAGUCCCAGCUACUGGGGAGGUUGAGGUACUAGAAUGCUUGAACCCAGGUGGUGGAGGCUGCAGUGAGCAGAGGUUGCAUCAGUGCACUCCCGCUUGGGUGACAGAGUGAGACUGUCUCAGAAAAAAAAAAAAAAGAA